AACAGAAGUUUCUCACCUAGGAAUGCGAGGGGCGCUCCCGCAUCUCCUGCACAUCUCCACCCCUGCGCAGGAGGAGAUCCCCAGGCUGCUCUCUCCAUCUCUCCUACAGCUCCCUGCAAACGAGGGGGAAGCUGCUGAGAGUCCCUAUCACUGCUGGCCUUUUAAUGUUGUAUGCAAGGAGGAAGAGGGCGAGGGAUAACUUGGUGCUGGACAACUGACCUGCGGCCCGAAGGGCCUCUGGGGAGGGGGUGCAAAAGAGGAGCGGCUGGGCUGGGGGACUCCAUGCGGGGGCGAUGGACAGGGCGGCGCUCCUGGGACUGGCCCGCUUGUGCGCGCUGUGGGCAGCCCUGCUCGUGCUGUUCCCCUACGGAGCCCAAGGAAACUGGAUGUGGUUGGGCAUUGCCUCCUUCGGGGUUCCAGAGAAGCUGGGCUGCGCCAAUUUGCCGCUGAACAGCCGCCAGAAGGAGCUGUGCAAGAGGAAACCGUACCUGCUGCCGAGCAUCCGAGAGGGCGCCCGGCUGGGCAUUCAGGAGUGCGGGAGCCAGUUCAGACACGAGAGAUGGAACUGCAUGAUCACCGCCGCCGCCACUACCGCCCCGAUGGGCGCCAGCCCCCUCUUUGGCUACGAGCUGAGCAGCGGCACCAAAGAGACAGCAUUUAUUUAUGCUGUGAUGGCUGCAGGCCUGGUGCAUUCUGUGACCAGGUCAUGCAGUGCAGGCAACAUGACAGAGUGUUCCUGUGACACCACCUUGCAGAACGGCGGCUCAGCAAGUGAAGGCUGGCACUGGGGGGGCUGCUCCGAUGAUGUCCAGUAUGGCAUGUGGUUCAGCAGAAAGUUCCUAGAUUUCCCCAUCGGAAACACCACGGGCAAAGAAAACAAAGUACUAUUAGCAAUGAACCUACAUAACAAUGAAGCUGGAAGGCAGGCUGUCGCCAAGUUGAUGUCAGUAGACUGCCGCUGCCACGGAGUUUCCGGCUCCUGUGCUGUGAAAACAUGCUGGAAAACCAUGUCUUCUUUUGAAAAGAUUGGCCAUUUGUUGAAGGAUAAAUAUGAAAACAGUAUCCAGAUAUCAGACAAAACAAAGAGGAAAAUGCGCAGGAGAGAAAAAGAUCAGAGGAAAAUACCAAUCCAUAAGGAUGAUCUGCUCUAUGUUAAUAAGUCUCCCAACUACUGUGUAGAAGAUAAGAAACUGGGAAUCCCAGGGACACAAGGCAGAGAAUGCAACCGUACAUCAGAGGGUGCAGAUGGCUGCAACCUCCUCUGCUGUGGCCGAGGUUACAACACCCAUGUGGUCAGGCACGUGGAGAGGUGUGAGUGUAAGUUCAUCUGGUGCUGCUAUGUCCGUUGCAGGAGGUGUGAAAGCAUGACUGAUGUCCACACUUGCAAGUAACCACUCCAUCCAGCCUUGGGCAAGAUGCCUCAGCAAUAUACAAUGGCAUUGCAACCAGAGAGGUGCCCAUCCCUGUGCAGCGCUAGUAAAGUUGACUCUUGCAGUGGAAUCCCUAGAACCUUGGACCUGAGAGUUUCCCUUACCUGAUCGACAUAUUUUCCUUUAUCUGAUCAACCCAUCAAUCAUGUGGAUUUCUUGGGAUUCUAAUGUUGAAAAGGUUUAUAUUCACCUUUUGAUGAUUUGGGGAAUAUAUAUUGACAUACAAGGAAGAUAAUCUGUUUCCUAAGCAAGAAAUAACAGGAAAGAUCCCUUAUGCCAGGAGGCCUGCCAUACUCAGGAUAAGAUCCUUGAAUAUGGAACUUAGUUACAGGACUCAAUAAUGGUGGGUGAACAUUAGUCAUUUUUAAAAGACACCUCUUAUAGCAAUAAGGAGACAUUAACAUGAAUCUCAUUUAUUCUCUCAGUAUUUUAACUGAAGAAAUUAUACUGUUUGUGUGUGGAUAGAAGAUGUUGAAAAGUUAACAUAAGCAUUGGGUGCUGACUUACCCUUUCAUGUACUUCCAAAGAAAGGUAAUCAAAAAGAAUCUUCUUAAGUGAUAUAAUAUCCCUAAAAAAAUGAUCAUUACAGAUGUUUAGUGACAAAGAAUCAAUAUGUAAAAAGUAUAAUGAAUGAUUUAGAUUUUAAGUGCCUUUUCACUGGGAGAAUCUGGAAAAACCUCCAUAAGGUAUAUAGCAAUCUUUGAUCUUUAGAUUCAUACUUUUAUCACAGAUCAGUUUCAACUGUUAAAAACCCACCUCUGAGAUACUGGGGGGAGGAUCCUGAAACAUGCGGGAAAAGGAGAGGUAAACAGUGGAGGUAAAAAUAUAAUUUCAUACAUUGUAAAGAAAAGCACCCUUUAAAUGUGUAAAGACAGUGUUUUGUAAAGAAUUUUGUUUAAAAAGUUUCUAUUUUGUAAAUACAGUACUUAAGUUAUAUGAUUUAUAUUAAAACAUUUAUUGACAAAGCCUAAGAGCUAAGGCAGUAAAAUUAUCUCAUAAAUAAUAUUAGCUUAUUUUUUUUCAUACUAUUAAUGCUAUUUUUUUGGACAUCGAAGAGAAUUUAACUUAGCAGUUAGUUAUAUGGAUGUGUAUUUCUUGCUAAAAUGACAGUUUUAUAUGUUAUAGAUUAAAAUAUGUUGCAAAAUAUCAAAAAUUUGUGUUAUUUCAGCAGUAAGAUUAAUUGAAUUCUCUUUUCACAUUAGUUAUGCUUAACUCAUAAGGUUAUUAUAAUAAAUUAUAUUAGUAAAAGUCUUAACUGGAAAAAAGAAUCUAAAUCAGAAUAGUGAUCAAUUUGUGGAUUUGAUAUCCUGGAUAUUUAUUAUAUUUUAUGUAAUGCUGCAUUUCUAUUUGAAUGUUAAGUGGUCUUUCUUGUUUUUAAUAUUCAUGCAUGUAUAUUCAUCAUAUUUUACAAGGUUCCUGGUAAAAAUUACAGGGCUCUAUUUAAGGAUGUAUUUUAAUGUAAAUGCUUAUGUUUUUUAUGAAUUGUUAAAUAUUUCAGUAUUAUAUAGAAAAAAAUAGAUUUUUAAAAUUCAGAAUGGACAAAGAGAAUAUUCAUUUUCUUAUUAAUAAGAUAAAGAAAUGUUUCCCUGCCCCACAGUCUUCAUUCUAUUUCUCUUUAAUUUUAUUCACUGAGGCAGAGAAACAAUUUUUGAAAAAGAGCAAACCCAUGGAAAAUGUCUCAGAUCUAAUAUUAAAAUCAAGACUAAGCAUUUAACUGUGA